AGAAAAAGUUUUCUUUUCUGGAGUCCCAAACGAGGUGCGGGACGGAAGAGGGGGUGAAGGCCAGAGGCUCGGGGCUUCAAGACCGCUGUCUGGAGUCCCCCUUUCCAGGCCAUGUCGGGGCCCACCUGGCUGCCCCCGAAGCAGCCGGAGCCCGCCAGAGCCCCUCAGGGGAGGGCGAUCCCCCGCGGCACCCCGGGGCCACCACCGGCCCACGGAGCAGCACUCCAGCCCCACCCCAGGGUCAAUUUUUGCCCCCUUCCAUCUGAGCAGUGUUACCAGGCCCCAGGGGGACCGGAGGAUCGGGGGCCGGCGUGGGUGGGGUCCCAUGGAGUACUCCAGCACACGCAGGGGCUCCCUGCAGACAGGGGGGGCCUUCGCCCUGGAAGCCUGGACGCCGAGAUAGACUUGCUGAGCAGCACGCUGGCCGAGCUGAAUGGGGGUCGGGGUCAUGCGUCACGGCGACCAGACCGACAGGCAUAUGAGCCCCCGCCACCUCCUGCCUACCGCACGGGCUCCCUGAAGCCAAAUCCAGCCUCGCCGCUCCCAGCGUCUCCCUAUGGGGGCCCCACUCCAGCCUCUUACACUACCGCCAGCACCCCGGCUGGCCCAGCCUUCCCCGUGCAAGUGAAGGUGGCACAGCCAGUGAGGGGCUGCGGCCCACCCAGGCGGGGAGCCUCUCAGGCCUCUGGGCCCCUCCCGGGCCCCCACUUUCCUCUCCCAGGCCGAGGUGAAGUCUGGGGGCCUGGCUAUAGGAGCCAGAGAGAGCCAGGGCCAGGGGCCAAAGAGGAAGCUGCUGGGGUCUCUGGCCCUGCAGGAAGAGGAAGAGGAGGCGAGCACGGGCCCCAGGUGCCCCUGAGCCAGCCUCCAGAGGAUGAGCUGGAUAGGCUGACGAAGAAGCUGGUUCACGACAUGAACCACCCGCCCAGCGGGGAGUACUUUGGCCAGUGUGGUGGCUGCGGAGAAGAUGUGGUUGGGGAUGGGGCUGGGGUUGUGGCCCUUGAUCGCGUCUUUCACGUGGGCUGCUUUGUAUGUUCUACAUGCCGGGCCCAGCUUCGCGGCCAGCAUUUCUACGCCGUGGAGAGGAGGGCAUAUUGCGAGGGCUGCUACGUGGCCACCCUGGAGAAAUGUGCCACGUGCUCCCAGCCCAUCCUGGACCGGAUCCUGCGGGCUAUGGGGAAGGCCUACCACCCUGGCUGCUUCACCUGCGUGGUGUGUCACCGCGGCCUCGACGGCAUCCCCUUCACAGUGGAUGCUACGAGCCAGAUCCACUGCAUUGAGGACUUUCACAGGAAGUUUGCCCCAAGAUGCUCAGUGUGCGGUGGGGCCAUAAUGCCUGAGCCAGGUCAGGAGGAGACUGUGAGAAUUGUUGCUCUGGAUCGAAGUUUUCACAUUGGCUGUUACAAGUGCGAGGAGUGUGGGCUGCUGCUCUCCUCUGAGGGCGAGUGUCAGGGCUGCUACCCGCUGGAUGGGCACAUCUUGUGCAAGGCCUGCAGCGCCUGGCGCAUCCAGGAGCUCUCAGCCACCGUCACCACUGACUGCUGAGUCUUCCUAGAAGUACCUGCUGGGUUCUCAGUUCCAGUUCCCAUCCUUUGAUUGAUCACUCUCCCUGACAUCCACCUGUAUGACUUUGUCACCAAAUGCUGUCUUCUCUUUCUCCAAUCAAGAAAUAAUAAUCCCUCGAGUUUACAAAACA